AAACGUCCGCCGGCGCGGGGACUGGGAGUCCAGGGCUCCAGCUCGGGGACCCGAGGCCAGCGACAGACAGCGGAGGGGUGGCCAUCGCGGACCCCGCCGGGGAGCGGAGGCGCAGAUUCCCUGGAGGCAGGAGCUCUGUCCAGUGACUCGGCCGGACCCGGGGCAGGGGCGCCCCGAGGACCUCGCAGGGCCCCCGAAAGGCCCCAAGGCGCGGCGUGCAGUGAGCGGGAAGUGGUUGGCCGGCGCCCCGCGGCGGCGCACAGCUCCUGACAGCCACGAUGCCGCCCGCGACCACGGUCUCCCUCCGGGAGCUGGCGGACCUCUCCAUCGGCACGCCAGAGGUGGGCGCCGUCAACUUCACGGCCCUGCACACGCUCAUCGUGGCCAUGCUCAAGAACCUCGACCUCCAAAAUACCCGGAUCGACUUCCAGCCCUCGUCGCCCGAGCCCAGCCGCUCGCUGCAGUCCGUCCGGAGCUCGUUCAGCAUCCCGCACCUGCCCGCGCCCAAGGAGGUGCCCAAGGGGGCGCCCCGGGAGAAGCGCAGGGGCGUGGGCCAGGCGCCUUCGUCAGCGCUGGAGAGCCAAGUGAAGGACCUGGGCGGCCAGGUGGAGGACCUGAGCAAGCAGCUCAAGCGUGUGGACGGCCAGGUGCAGGGCAUCGCCACGCACGUGCAGCACUUCUCCCAGGCCAGCGGGCUUGACCUGGCCGCGCUAGAGUGGCCGGAGGAGCAGGAGGUGGGCGUGCGGGCGUUCGAUAGGGUGCGGACUGGGAGUAUCAUGAAGGACGCCGCCGAGGAGCUCAGCUUUGCCAGGGUACUUUUACAGCGGGUUGAUGAACUAGAGAAGCUAUUCAAAGAUCGGGAGCAAUUCCUGGAACUAGUCAGCCGGAAGCUGAGUUUGGUUCCUGGUGCAGAAGAAGUCACCAUGGUCACCUGGGAAGAGCUGGAGCAGGCGAUUACGGACGGCUGGAGAGCCUCACAAGCGGGCUCAGAAACACUUAUGGGAUUUUCUAAGCACGGAGGGUUCACUUCCUUAACAUCACCUGAAGGGACUCUAAGCGGAGACUCUACCAAGCAACCAAGUAUUGAGCAGGCUCUGGAUUCUGCCAGUGGUCUUGGCCCGGAUCGGACUGCAUCAGGAUCUGGUGGCACAGCACACCCCUCUGAUGGGGUUUCCAGUAGGGAACAAAGCAAGGUCCCCUCUGGUACUGGGAGACAGCAGCAGCCGAGGGCCCGUGAUGAAGCUGGCGUGCCACGACUCCAUCAGUCUUCUACAUUCCAAUUCAAAUCAGACUCAGAUCGUCACAGGAGUAGAGAGAAGCUUACCUCGACACAACCAAGAAGAAAUGCACGUCCUGGUCCAGUUCAACAGGACUUACCCUUGGCCAGAGACCAGCCCAGUAGUGUGCCCGCUAGCCAGAGUCAGGUCCAUCUAAGGCCAGAUCGUCGUGGGUUAGAACCAACUGGCAUGAAUCAGCCUGGAUUAGUGCCUGCUAGCACUUACCCACAUGGUGUGGUACCCCUCAGCAUGGGUCAGCUUGGUGUGCCACCACCUGAAAUGGAUGAUCGGGAAUUGAUACCAUUUGUCGUGGAUGAGCAACGUAUGUUGCCACCAUCAGUACCUGGCAGAGACCAGCAAGGAUUGGAACUACCUAGCACAGACCAACAUGGUCUGGUUUCAGUCAGUGCAUAUCAGCAUGGUAUGACAUUUCCUGGCACAGACCAACGCAGUAUGGAACCACUUGGCAUGGAUCAGCGUGGAUGUGUAAUAUCAGGCAUGGGUCAGCAAGGACUAGUACCCCCUGGUAUAGACCAGCAAGGAUUGACAUUGCCUGUCGUCGAUCAACAUGGCCUGGUUCUACCUUUUACAGACCAGCAUGGUUUGGUAUCACCUGGUUUGAUGCCAAUUAGUGCAGAUCAGCAAGGUUUUGUGCAGCCCAGUUUGGAAGCAACUGGCUUCAUACAACCUGGCACAGAGCAGCAUGAUUUGAUCCAGUCUGGCAGAUUUCAGCGUGCUUUGGUGCAGCGUGGUGCAUAUCAGCCUGGCUUGGUCCAACCUGGUGCAGAUCAGCGUGGUUUGGUCCGGCCUGGAAUGGAUCAGUCUGGUUUGGCCCAACCUGGUGCAGAUCAGCGUGGUUUGGUCUGGCCUGGAAUGGAUCAGUCUGGUUUGGCCCAACCUGGUAGAGAUCAGCAUGGUUUGAUCCAGCCUGGCACAGGUCAGCAUGAUUUGGUCCAAUCUGGCACAGGUCAGGGUGUCUUGGUACAGCCUGGUGUAGAUCAGCCUGGCAUGGUCCAACCUGGCAGAUUUCAGCGUGCUUUGGUGCAGCCUGGUGCAUAUCAGCCUGGCUUGGUCCAACCUGGUGCAGAUCAGAUUGAUGUGGUGCAACCUGGUGCAGAUCAGCAUGGUUUGGUACAAUCUGGUGCAGAUCAGAGUGAUUUGGCUCAACCUGGUGCAGUUCAGCAUGGUUUGGUCCAACCUGGAGUAGAUCAGCGUGGUUUGGCACAACCUCGUGCAGAUCAUCAGCGUGGUUUGGUCCCACCUGGUGCAGAUCAGCGUGGUUUGGUCCAACCUGGUGCAGAUCAGCAUGGUUUGGUCCAACCUGGAGUGGAUCAGCAUGGUUUGGCACAACCUGGUGAAGUUCAGCGUAGUUUGGUGCAACCUGGUAUAGUUCAGCGUGGUUUGGUGCAACCUGGUGCAGUUCAGCGUGGUUUGGUGCAACCUGGUGCAGUUCAGCGUGGUUUGGUCCAACCUGGAGUGGAUCAGCGUGGUUUGGUUCAACCUGGUGCAGUUCAGCGUGGUUUGGUCCAACCUGGUGCAGUUCAGCAUGGUUUGGUCCAACCUGGUGCAGAUCAGCGUGGUUUGGUCCAACCUGGAGUGGAUCAGCGUGGUUUGGUGCAACCUGGAGUGGAUCAGCGUGGUUUGGUCCAACCUGGAAUGGACCAGCGUGGUUUGAUCCAACCUGGUGCAGAUCAGCCUGGUUUGGUCCAGCCUGGUGCAGGUCAGCUGGGUAUGGUGCAGCCUGGAAUAGGUCAGCAAGGUAUGGUGCAACCUCAGGCAGAUCCACAUGGCCUGGUACAACCUGGUGCCUAUCCUCUUGGUUUGGUACAACCUGGUGCAUAUUUGCAUGAUUUAUCUCAAUCUGGGACAUAUCCACGUGGUCUGGUGCAGCCAGGAAUGGAUCAGUAUGGUUUGAGACAACCUGGUGCAUAUCAGCCAGGCUUGAUAGCACCAGGCACAAAGCUUCGUGGCUCUUCAACAUUCCAGGCAGAUUCUACAGGUUUUAUAUCAGUACGUCCAUAUCAACAUGGUAUGGUACCUCCUGGCAGAGAACAAUACGGCCAGGUGUCACCACUCCUAGCCAGUCAAGGUUUGGCAUCACCUGGUAUAGAUCGAAGGAGUUUGGUACCACCAGAAACUUAUCAGCAAGGUUUGAUGCAUCCUGGCACAGACCAGCACAGCCCAAUACCACUGAGUACAGGUUUGGGAUCUACACACCCAGAUCAACAGCAUGUGGCAUCACCUGGCCCAGGUGAGCAUGACCAGGUAUACCCAGAUGCAGCUCAGCAUGGCCAUGCUUUCUCUCUCUUUGACAGUCAUGAUUCAAUGUAUCCUGGUUAUCGUGGCCCAGGGUAUCUAAGUGCUGAUCAGCAUGGCCAGGAAGGUUUGGAUCCAAAUAGAACACGAGCCUCGGACCGACAUGGAAUUCCUGCCCAGAAGGCCCCAGGCCAAGAUGUCACUCUUUUCAGGAGUCCAGACUCCGUCGACCGAGUCUUAUCAGAAGGGAGCGAAGUCUCGAGUGAAGUCCUGAGUGAGCGACGCAAUUCACUGCGUAGAAUGAGUUCUAGUUUCCCCACGGCAGUGGAGACAUUUCAUCUGAUGGGAGAGCUCAGUAGCCUCUAUGUGGGGCUAAAGGAGAGUAUGAAGGAUCUGGAUGAGGAGCAGGCCGGCCAAACCGACUUGGAGAAGAUCCAGUUCCUGCUGGCACAGAUGGUCAAAAGGACCAUACCUCCUGAACUGCAGGAGCAGCUGAAGACCGUAAAGACGCUAGCCAAAGAAGUUUGGCAGGAGAAAGCAAAAGUGGAAAGGCUGCAGAGGAUCCUGGAAGGGGAAGGGAAUCAAGAAGCAGGGAAGGAACUGAAAGCUGGAGAGCUGAGAUUGCAGCUGGGUGUCCUCAGAGUCACCGUGGCUGACAUAGAAAAGGAGCUGGCCGAGUUGAGGGAGAGCCAAGACAGGGGCAAGGCUGCCAUGGAAAAUUCUGUCUCUGAAGCCUCCCUUUACCUGCAGGACCAGUUGGACAAGCUCAGGAUGAUCAUUGAGAGCAUGCUGACCUCCUCCUCCACGCUCCUGUCCAUGAGCAUGGCCCCGCACAAGGCCCACACCUUGGCUCCUGGCCAGAUCGACCCUGAGGCCACCUGUCCAGCCUGCAGCCUGGAUGUGAGCCAUCAGGUCAGCACGCUGGUGCGGCGCUAUGAGCAACUCCAAGACAUGGUCAACAGCCUGGCCGUCUCCCGACCCUCCAAGAAGGCCAAGCUCCAGAGACAGGACGAGGAGCUGCUGGGCCGUGUGCAGAGUGCCAUCCUGCAGGUGCAGGGUGACUGCGAGAAGCUCAACAUCACCACCAGCAACCUCAUCGAGGACCAUCGGCAGAAACAGAAGGACAUUGCUAUGCUGUACCAGGGUCUGGAGAAGCUCGAAAAGGAAAAGGCCAACAGGGAGCACCUGGAGAUGGAGAUCGAUGUGAAAGCCGACAAGAGUGCUCUGGCCACCAAAGUGAGCCGUGUCCAGUUUGAUGCCACCACGGAGCAGCUGAACCACAUGAUGCAGGAGCUGGUGGCCAAGAUGAGCGGGCAGGAGCAGGACUGGCAGAAGAUGCUGGACAGGCUGCUCACAGAGAUGGACAACAAGCUGGACCGCCUGGAGCUGGACCCAGUGAAGCAGUUGCUGGAGGAUCGGUGGAAAUCGCUGCGACAGCAGCUCAGGGAGCGCCCCCCACUCUACCAGGCAGACGAGGCGGCUGCCAUGCGGAGGCAGCUCCUGGCACAUUUCCACUGCCUCUCAUGUGACCGGCCCUUGGAGACACCUGUGACUGGACAUGCCAUCCCCGUGACCCCCGCGGGUCCAGGCCUACCUGGGCACCAUUCCAUCCGCCCCUACACGGUGUUUGAACUGGAGCAGGUCCGGCAGCAUAGCCGCAACCUCAAGCUGGGCAGCGCCUUCCCUCGGGGUGACCUGGCGCAGAUGGAGCAGAGCGUGGGGCGCCUGCGCUCCAUGCACUCCAAGAUGCUGAUGAACAUUGAGAAGGUGCAGAUCCACUUCGGGGGCUCCACCAAGGCCAGCAGCCAGAUAAUCCGCGAGCUGCUGCACGCCCAGUGCCUGGGCUCCCCCUGCUACAAACGGGUGACAGAUAUGGCUGAUUACACCUACUCAACUGUGCCCCGGCGCUGCGGGGGCAGCCACACCCUCACCUACCCCUACCACCGCAGCCGCCCGCAGCACCUUCCCCGGGGCCUGUAUCCUACUGAAGAGAUCCAGAUUGCCAUGAAGCAUGAUGAGGUGGACAUCUUGGGCCUGGAUGGCCACAUUUACAAGGGACGGAUGGACACAAGGCUGCCAGGCAUCCUCCGAAAAGACAGCUCAGGGACCUCAAAGCGCAAGUCCCAGCAGCCCAGGCCCCACGUGCACAGGCCGCCAUCCCUCAGCAGCAAUGGCCAGCUGCCCUCUCGGCCACAGAGCGCCCAGAUUUCGGCUGGCAACACCUCAGGUAGCUUCCCUCUGGGUGGGGCGUCCUGCCAGGCCUCCCCGCUGGCCCUGCCGGCCCCCUUUCCUGCUCAUGUAGGGCCUUUAUCUCCCCGGAGAGGGGAGGGCCUGGGAGCCGAAGGGGGGGAUGGGUGUGGAAAAGAGGAACCCCGAGUGACUGAGUGAUUUGUGCCCCUUCUGGGAGGUGGGUAGGUGCUGUUACUGUCCCAUUCCACAGAAGAUGAAAUAGGGACAGGGUCACCACCCACAUCUCUGGCUCCAGGUCCAUGCCCUUGCCCUGCUCACGUGCACUCACUGUCAUGGAGCUCGUGCGCCUGGGCUCUGCAUGGUGGCUGCUGGGCACAGGCCAUGCCCGGGUCCCCAAGAGGCCACGACCCUGUCAUGGAGGAACCUCUCUCUGCCUCCCGCCUGGAAGAUCCCUUGGGUCCUUGAUCUCCGCAGGAGCUAAGUUGGGCCUGAAGGUCAGGAGGGUUUGGUAACAAGGCCCUGCAGCCAGGAGGCUGGAUCACUGACAAGUGACCCUGGGCAAGGUCACUCUUGACAAGGGCUCUCCCCUCUCCAGACCUCAGUUUCCUCGUCUGUCAUCAAGGGGGUGCUGGGUUAGUGCUGCUUGGAGUCAGGCCCCCCCCAAGAAUCUAAUAAAAGCUGCCGACCUUCCUCCUGUAAAACAGUUAUGCACCCACAUUCCUUGUGAAUGUCUGUGGGAGGUUCAGGGACCCUCCCCAACCAGAGCCUCCACCCUCCCCUGCCCCUCGGCUAGAUGCUCUCCAGCAUCACUCCAGCCCUCAGUGAGGACCCGGCGCUGAGGGAGGAGGAAAUCACAACAGAAAAGUGGCUGCGGUGCUCAUGGCUCCUCAGCAUCAUCCAGGGCCCCCCACAGACCAGGUAGUUUAGGAGCUUUACAUGGACGAACCACUUUCAAUCUAUGUACCAGCACUUAGAGGUAGGGGCCGUUAGCACCACUUACAGCUGAGAAAACUGAGGCACAGAGAGGUGAAGGUCCUUGCUCUAGGUCACACAGCCAGGAAGCGGCAGAGCUGGAGUUCAAAGCCAAGCCCUCUGGCCCAGAGGCUGUGCUGGGAACGGCAGGUCUCAGUGGUGGACAGUGAGCACAUGACUGUCACCCUGGCUCCCAGAACUCUGUUUUCUUGGGAAUACUUAGCUCCCUUCUCCCAGUGUCUACUCUAAGGGCACUGAAAAUGCCCUGGAAGCAGGAGAGAGGGACUGGUAGUCUCAGGAAAAUUCCUGUGCCUGUUGGUGUGGAUGUCACCUCGUGUCUGUAUUAACAGGAAACAGUACCAAAGAGGCAGCUCUUGGCUCCUGCAGAAGGACGUGUUUGCUUAUUUUUCAUUCACAAGAUCAUGAAGGGUGCUUCAUGACUGCUUAGGAGCUCAGAUGGGCCUGCGCCGUGCCCCCCGGCCCCGGCAGCUCCCCUCCAGCCUGUGUCAGCCCAGCAUGGCGAACAGAACUGCUCUCAACCUCCCUGGGCAUUGGGCAGGCUGGGGUGACCCCUGGUGGGCUUGGGGAAUGUGUUGAGCAACCUCAGCACCCCUGUCUUACAGUUUCUUCUCGUCAACAGAAAGAUAGACCUUCCUCCGAGGGCCGUCUCUCCCAGCCGAACACAGCCCACCCGCCCAGCUCCGCCGCGGUGGCAAACAGGGGGCUGGAGAGGCACGUGGACAUGCCUCCUGGGGAGGGGCUCGAGGAGCCCACGCGGGGGCCGCGGUCCAGCACCGCUCAGUGAGCGGAGGUGUAAAUAAACAUUCAGGAGGAA